CUGGGCGCCUGGCUGGCCGGGCUGGUCCUGCGGCCGCGGGUGAGUCUCGUCCGCUCGCGCUGCCCACCGCGGCUCCAGCAGCUCCAGGCGCGGUUCCCCGGCCCGCGCCGCUCCCGGCCCCCCGGCUCGGGCGCCUCCCGCCGCAGCGCAGGCUCCCCCGCCGGCCGGGCUCCUGCGCGGCGCGGCUCGGCUCAUGCCCCCGGGCGCGGGGCACACAGGCCGGCCGGCAGCCGCUGGGAAAUAGGCCCCCGGGGGCGGUGGCGGCGGCGGGGCCAUGGCGCGGAGACCCCGGGCGCCGGCCGCCUCCGGGGAGGAGUUCUCCUUCGUCAGCCCGCUGGUGAAAUACCUGCUCUUCUUCUUCAACAUGCUCUUCUGGGUGAUUUCCAUGGUGAUGGUGGCUGUGGGUGUCUACGCUCGGCUAAUGAAGCAUGCAGAAGCAGCCCUAGCCUGCCUGGCAGUGGACCCUGCCAUCCUGCUGAUCGUGGUGGGUGUCCUCAUGUUCCUGCUCACCUUCUGUGGCUGCAUUGGGUCCCUCCGCGAGAACAUCUGCCUCCUGCAGACGUUCUCCCUCUGCCUCACCGCUGUGUUCCUGCUGCAGCUGGCCGCUGGGAUCCUGGGCUUCGUCUUCUCAGACAAGGCUCGAGGGAAAGUGAGUGAGAUCAUCAACAAUGCCAUUGUGCACUACCGAGAUGACUUGGAUCUGCAGAACCUCAUUGAUUUUGGCCAGAAAAAGUUUAGCUGCUGUGGAGGGAUUUCCUACAAGGACUGGUCUCAGAACAUGUAUUUCAACUGCUCAGAAGACAACCCCAGUCGAGAGCGCUGCUCUGUGCCUUACUCCUGUUGCUUGCCUACUCCUGACCAGGCAGUGAUCAACACUAUGUGUGGCCAAGGUAUGCAGGCCUUUGACUACUUGGAAGCUAGCAAAGUCAUCUACACCAAUGGCUGUAUUGACAAGUUGGUCAACUGGAUACACAGCAACCUAUUCUUACUUGGUGGUGUGGCUCUAGGCCUGGCCAUCCCCCAGCUGGUGGGAAUUCUGCUGUCCCAGAUCCUAGUGAAUCAGAUCAAAGAUCAGAUCAAGCUACAGCUCUACAACCAGCAGCACCGGGCUGACCCAUGGUACUGAGAAUCCAUCCUGCACCUCCUCACCAUGGAAACUGGCAAGCCUCAUAAACGAACAGCAGUGGGUGCUGAAAGCAGCACCAAAUGGAGAUUUGGAUUCCAGCCCCCCAGUGACAGCCCAGUGGGAAGAAGCAAACUCCAGAUGGGCAGAAGGCAGGGUGCACAGGUGGCUCCAGUCUCAGGAGGAUGCGCCUCCUCUCCCCCAUCCCAGCCCUCAGCAUUGUGCCAGAGUGAUACCCUUAAGUGUUUGGGUUUAUGUUUUCAGUUUUGUUUGGGAAACAGCAGUUGCACAGAGAGUUGGGGGUACUGCUGCUGCCUUUUCACCGAGGCACUGCCACCACCAGCUCUAGCAGGGAUGCUCCUGAGCUUGGCGGACAUACUUAGAUCCUAACGUGCCAGUGAGACCUGGCUGUGGAGAGUAGCACUGGCAGCCCUGCCUGGACUCCACUUGGCAUGAUACCAGCUCCAGAAGGGAAGGGAGUGGAGCAGGCAGUGAGGAGAGAGCCUGGGGGUCGGCUGGGGACAGCCGUAUGUGCUAGGUAGGAGUGGAGGGAGAUAUGUUUACCAAAUGCCUGUCCUGCCAUCCUCCCAGGUAGUCAGAGUGAGCUACAUCCUGCCCCGCCUUCAUUUCCAUGGAAACAUGGCAGCUAGGACACGGGGUACAACAGCAGCCAAAUUCUUCCCCACCUCCCUUACUUCGAAAAAAAGUUUGGAACCCUGGUCCCUAUACUCUGCAGUCAGAAGUGGGACUGAGCCAUACAUGCCCUUGAAUUCCUCCCUGUCUGGCCCUCCCUCUCCAGCAAGCAGGGUUUUCUUUAACUUGGCAGUGUGCAGAGGAGAAGUGGUAACACCCCCACCCCAUUCCCCUGCAUCGGAGCUCAGUAUUCCUACAGGGUAAGAGGUAGGAAUCUUGCUGGGACGAGGGGAGCCAGAAGUGGCAAUAAAAGCGUGUUGACCUGGGCUACGCGGGACUCCAUGAAUUUUCCAUUCUGGCAACUGGAAGGGGAGGUGUAGAAGGGCCCUGCAGAGGACGGCACUGGAGACUCUCCUAAACGCCACACACCUCCCCCUUGCUGCCCGCCACACGCGCGUCUCCUUCAACCGAUGCAUUGCCACCCUCCCACAGCCUCGCCCUCUGCUCUAAAUUAGGUCGAAAGAGUCCCAGUUCCAAUCUAGGAACAGCAUAAUUUUGUUCCAAAACCUGAUCUGUGUUUUUCUAAUUAAAAUUAAUUUGUCACCCAAAACAGGAGGGGGAUGGGGAGGAGGGACAUGAGCACUCCGCUGGGGCCGGGACGGGGAAUGAGGAGGAAGAAGGCCCUCUCUUCCCCUACCCGGGCCCUCCAGGACCUUCUCCCUGAGUCGGCUGUAGGGAGGACUCCGAGGAAGCUCGGCGCGGUGCGCUGGGCCUCCUGGCGCCGGGAGGAGCGCGCGAGGCAGGCGGGGCGGGCGCGUCCGGGGCGGGGCGCUGGACUUCGUGGGUGGUCCCCGCCCCCGCGGCGGCCUAGGCCCGCGCCUGCGUCCCCCAACCCGGAGGAGAUGGGGGGCUGUGCUAGCUGCUUGCCCAGCGAGUGUUCCCGGAGUCUCCUCGCCGCACCCCGCUAUCGGGCGCUCAGACCAGGGGCUCGGCCUGGCGGGAAAUAGCCUCGACCGAACUGCUGCGGGGACAAAGAGCCGCGAGUUCGCUCCCUGCCCCCAGUGUCUCCUAAGCGAGCCUUCUGCUCCUAGGAAGGCGCCUUUCCAGCAGCCGCUGGGACCCUGGCCAGUGUUUAGCUCCCAACUAGUAACAGACGGAAAGAAAAAAUAAAAUUAUCCAGAAUCUAGAAUAAAAA